GCGCGCAGAUCGCUCCGGACCCGGACACCGCCUGCGAGGAGCGCCGACCAGCCGGGAAGGGUUCGCGCUAGGCGGCGCCCGGGUCCCGUCGGCCAGGGUGAGCGUCCGGCCCGCGUCCGCGCCACGCCCGCCGCGUUCCCCUUUCCUCUGCGGCGGGCCGAGAGAUAACCCUGCCCGAGGGGUCCCGGCGCCCGCCCCCCACGCGGUCGCACUGGAAUUCGCAGCCCCUCUCGGGUCCCCGGGGCGCAUUUUGCAGUCUGAGUGGCAAUGCACUUGCUCCAGGACAGGCGGCUACCCCGCCGCAGCGGAGGCGCGGACUUUUCUUUUGGGGGGUCUCGCCGGCUCGCCGCGCUCCCCACCUUGCCUGCGCCCGCCCGGAGCCAGCGGUUCUCCAAGCACCCAGCAUCCUGCUAGACGCGCCGCGCACCGACGGAGGGGACAUGGGCAGAGCAAUGGUGGCCAGGCUCGGGCUGGGGCUGCUGCUGCUGGCACUGCUCCUACCCACGCAGAUUUAUUCCAGUGAAACAACAACUGGAACUUCAAGUAACUCCUCCCAGAGUACUUCCAACUCUGGGUUGGCCCCAAAUCCAACUAAUGCCACCACCAAGGCGGCUGGUGGUGCCCUGCAGUCAACAGCCAGUCUCUUCGUGGUCUCACUCUCUCUUCUGCAUCUCUACUCUUAAGAGACUCAGGCCAAGAAACGUCUUCUAAAUUUCCCCAUCUUCUAAACCCAAUCCAAAUGGCGUCUGGAAGUCCAAUGUGGCAAGGAAAAACAGGUCUUCAUCGAAUCUACUAAUUCCACACCUUUUAUUGACACAGAAAAUGUUGAGAAUCCCAAAUUUGAUUGAUUUGAAGAACAUGUGAGAGGUUUGACUAGAUGAUGGAUGCCAAUAUUAAAUCUGCUGGAGUUUCAUGUACAAGAUGAAGGAGAGGCAACAUCCAAAAUAGUUAAGACAUGAUUUCCUUGAAUGUGGCUUGAGAAAUAUGGACACUUAAUACUACCUUGAAAAUAAGAAUAGAAAUAAAGGAUGGGAUUGUGGAAUGGAGAUUCAGUUUUCAUUUGGUUCAUUAAUUCUAUAAGGCCAUAAAACAGGUAAUAUAAAAAGCUUCCAUGAUUCUAUUUAUAUGUACAUGAGAAGGAACUUCCAGGUGUUACUGUAAUUCCUCAACGUAUUGUUUCGACAGCACUAAUUUAAUGCCGAUAUACUCUAGAUGAAGUUUUACAUUGUUGAGCUAUUGCUGUUCUCUUGGGAACUGAACUCACUUUCCUCCUGAGGCUUUGGAUUUGACAUUGCAUUUGACCUUUUAUGUAGUAAUUGACAUGUGCCAGGGCAAUGAUGAAUGAGAAUCUACCCCCAGAUCCAAGCAUCCUGAGCAACUCUUGAUUAUCCAUAUUGAGUCAAAUGGUAGGCAUUUCCUAUCACCUGUUUCCAUUCAACAAGAGCACUACAUUCAUUUAGCUAAACGGAUUCCAAAGAGUAGAAUUGCAUUGACCACGACUAAUUUCAAAAUGCUUUUUAUUAUUAUUAUUUUUUAGACAGUCUCACUUUGUCGCCCAGGCCGGAGUGCAGUGGUGCGAUCUCAGAUCAGUGUACCAUUUGCCUCCCGGGCUCAAGCGAUUCUCCUGCCUCAGCCUCCCAAGUAGCUGGGAUUACAGGCACCUGCCACCAUGCCCGGCUAAUUUUUGUAAUUUUAGUAGAGACAGGGUUUCACCAUGUUGCCCAGGCUGGUUUCGAACUCCUGACCUCAGGUGAUCCACCCGCCUCGGCCUCCCAAAGUGCUGGGAUUACAGGCUUGAGCCCCCGCGCCCAGCCAUCAAAAUGCUUUUUAUUUCUGCAUAUGUUGAAUACUUUUUACAAUUUAAAAAAAUGAUCUGUUUUGAAGGCAAAAUUGCAAAUCUUGAAAUUAAGAAGGCAAAAAUGUAAAGGAGUCAAAACUAUAAAUCAAGUAUUUGGGAAGUGAAGACUGGAAGCUAAUUUGCAUUAAAUUCACAAACUUUUAUACUCUUUCUGUAUAUACAUUUUUUUUCUUUAAAAAACAACUAUGGAUCAGAAUAGCCACAUUUAGAACACUUUUUGUUAUCAGUCAAUAUUUUUAGAUAGUUAGAACCUGGUCCUAAGCCUAAAAGUGGGCUUGAUUCUGCAGUAAAUCUUUUACAACUGCCUCGACACACAUAAACCUUUUUAAAAAUAGACACUCCCCGAAGUCUUUUGUUCGCAUGGUCACACACUGAUGCUUAGAUGUUCCAGUAAUCUAAUAUGGCCACAGUAGUCUUGAUGACCAAAGUCCUUUUUUUCCAUCUUUAGAAAACUACAUGGGAACAAACAGAUCGAACAGUUUUGAAGCUACUGUGUGUGUGAAUGAACACUCUUGCUUUAUUCCAGAAUGCUGUACAUCUAUUUUGGAUUGUAUAUUGUGUUUGUGUAUUUACGCUUUGAUUCAUAGUAACUUCUUAUGGAAUUGAUUUGCAUUGAACACAAACUGUAAAUAAAAAGAAAUGGCUGAAAGAGCAA